GGGACAGCGCCCGUAGGCAGCCCCACGGGCAGGGCGCGCGGGCGGGGCGGGGCGGGCCGGGCCAGAGGAGCGCCCGGCAUGUCGCAAGGGCUCCCGGCCGCCGGCAGCGUCCUGCAGAGGAGCGUCGCGGCGCCCGGGAACCAGCCGCAGCCGCAGCCGCAGCAGCAGAGCCCUGAGGAUGAUGACAGGAAGGUCCGAAGGAGAGAAAAAAACCGAGUUGCUGCUCAGAGAAGUCGGAAGAAGCAGACCCAGAAGGCUGACAAGCUCCAUGAGGAAUAUGAGAGCCUGGAGCAAGAAAACACCAUGCUGCGGAGAGAGAUCGGGAAGCUGACAGAGGAGCUGAAGCACCUGACAGAGGCACUGAAGGAGCACGAGAAGAUGUGCCCGCUGCUGCUCUGCCCUAUGAACUUUGUGCCAGUGCCUCCCCGGCCGGACCCUGUGGCCGGCUGCUUGCCCCGAUGAAGCCGGGGACACUCCUCUGCCCAGCAAGGAGCCUUGGUCAUUUUCAUACCUGGGAGGAAGGCUUUUCCUUCACAAUUGUAUACAGGGGGCACCUGUGGCCAGGCCUCCUCCUGGGAGCUCCAGGACCAGCCAGCUGUGUUCCCUGCAGACUGGGCUCAGCCCGACAUCCAACAGGCGCCAAACUCACAGAGCCCUUGUGCAGAUCCAGCAUGGAGGCCACCCUCAGGAGUGACUUCUCAUCCACCCUGGCAGCUAGUAGGUUCUGCUGUUAUGCAGAGCCAUUUCCUCUAGAAUUUGGAUAAUAAAGAUGCUUAUUGUCUCUCCCUUCUCCAGUUCUGGGAAUUUACAGGCACAAUACACUUCCUUUUCCUGGA